GGAGGCCCGAGCGAGGGACAAGACUCCGACUCCAGCUCUGACUUUUUUCGCGGCUCUCGCGCGAAUCCUAUCCAUUUCCUCCAGAAGAUGUCCAACAGUCACCAGUCUGGCAGCAGGGUGGGGCUUCCACUGCAGCCAUGUCACUCCUCUUGCUGGUGGUCUCAGCCCUUCACAUCCUCAUUCUUAUACUGCUUUUCGUGGCCACUUUGGACAAGUCCUGGUGGACUCUCCCUGGGAAAGAGUCCCUGAAUCUCUGGUACGACUGCACGUGGAACAACGACACCAAAACAUGGGCCUGCAGUAAUGUCAGCGAGAAUGGCUGGCUGAAGGCGGUGCAGGUCCUCAUGGUGCUCUCCCUCAUUCUCUGCUGUCUCUCCUUCAUCCUGUUCAUGUUCCAGCUCUACACCAUGCGACGAGGAGGUCUCUUCUAUGCCACCGGCCUCUGCCAGCUUUGCACCAGCGUGGCGGUGUUUACUGGCGCCUUGAUCUAUGCCAUUCACGCCGAGGAGAUCCUGGAGAAGCACCCGCGAGGGGGCAGCUUCGGAUACUGCUUCGCCCUGGCCUGGGUGGCCUUCCCCCUCGCCCUGGUCAGCGGCAUCAUCUACAUCCACCUACGGAAGCGGGAGUGAGCGCCCCGCCUCGCUCGGCUGCCCCCGCCCCUUCCCGGCCCCCCUCGCCGCGCGUCCUCCAAAAAAUAAAACCUUAACCGCGG